AGUCUUUGAGAGUCACAUCUCUUAUUUGGACCAGUAUAGACAGAAGUAAACCCAGCUGACUUGUUUCCUGGGACAGUUGAGUUAAGGGAUGGCUUUCACAGAGCAUUCACCGCUGACCCCUCACCGUCGGGACCUCUGUAGCCGCUCUAUCUGGCUAGCAAGGAAGAUUCGUUCAGACCUGACUGCUCUUACGGAAUCCUAUGUGAAGCAUCAGGGCCUGAACAAGAACAUCAACCUGGACUCUGCGGAUGGGAUGCCAGUGGCAAGCACUGAUCAGUGGAGUGAGCUGACCGAGGCAGAGCGACUCCAAGAGAACCUUCAAGCUUAUCGUACCUUCCAUGUUUUGUUGGCCAGGCUCUUAGAAGACCAGCAGGUGCAUUUUACCCCAACCGAAGGUGACUUCCAUCAAGCUAUACAUACCCUUCUUCUCCAAGUCGCUGCCUUUGCAUACCAGAUAGAGGAGUUAAUGAUACUCCUGGAAUACAAGAUCCCCCGCAAUGAGGCUGAUGGGAUGCCUAUUAAUGUUGGAGAUGGUGGUCUCUUUGAGAAGAAGCUGUGGGGCCUAAAGGUGCUGCAGGAGCUUUCACAGUGGACAGUAAGGUCCAUCCAUGACCUUCGUUUCAUUUCUUCUCAUCAGACUGGGAUCCCAGCACGUGGGAGCCAUUAUAUUGCUAACAACAAGAAAAUGUAGCAGUUAGUCCCUUCUCUCUUCCUUGCUUUCUCUUCUAAUGGAAUAUGCGUAGUUCCCUGGGGCCUCGCUUUCCCAUCUUAAAUUUCUAAAAACAGUUAAGACAACAGGCAUUUUCUUUCUUUUUUCUCUGACCACCUGCAGCCUGUUGAAGGACUACAGGUAUUUUCAUCAAGUAGCGUUGGAGACAUACACAAAUGGGCAUACAAGUUUAGCCUGGGGGGUGUGAUUUGUGUGCGUGCUUGCAUGUGCUGCAGGUGUAAGAGAGUGGGAGCAGGGACAACGUCCUUCCACUUCAGGGUUCUAACCUUUCUAACCCACUAAGUAACCUCUACAGGCAUUUAACUGCCUUACAGACAGAAUAUACAUAUGUUAAUUCUAGUCCUGGAUGACUCGGUCUGAGAAGAUUCAAUUUAAAAUCAGACUCUUUAGUUGAUUUAAACUCUUAGAGAAUAAGAAUAAUAAUGGCUAACUUUUAUUAUCUUCUAUAUUAAGGCAGUAUGCCAAGGGUCUUUAUGUAUAUUAUGUACAGCGUUUACAACCUUGUGAGCAAGGUGGUGUUACUCCCAUUAGGUAGAUGAGAAAACAGGCUCACAGAGAUUUGGUUAAGCUCACACAGCUAACAAGUAGCACACUGAGUUUGAACACAGAUCAUUCUCCUUGUAAAAGCCUAUGUGCCUUUCACUUUAGAGGCUUGAUCAUGAAUCACUGCACCUCUUUGUCACAGGGUGUUGGAAGAUGCAUCCAUGUAAUCUAUUCCCAUCGCUGGAAAACAGCUGCUGUUAGAUGUCCUCAGAAGUCAGUUGCAAAUUUUAGCGUUAAAGUCAGGAUUUAUUGUUCAUACUUGGCGGUGAGGAGGGCAGCUGGAGAUCUUAAGAUUCCAUUUUGGAAAAUGAUUAGGCCCGCCAAACUUCUGAACUUUGGAAGCUGGGGAUGUUUAGUAAUACAGCCUGGUUUUUAAGUACUCACUAAAAGUUCUCAAAUAUUGGGUUGGGCACGGCUUAUACCAGGUUACCUCACUUUUAAUUAGUGAUGCAGGCAGUGUAACCCAAGCAUUUGUGGACAAUGAGUGGAAUACUAAAGUUAAAAAGUCAAACUUUCACCUCAGAUUUUCUGGACUUAGUCAUGAGGAGAGGGUGAGGCCCACUCUGUUCCUACUGGAGAUACCAGAGACUCUGAAACUAUAGAAUAAAGCCUCUGUGCUGCACAACAAA